AGUCAGCCGCGUCGCGAAUGGGGCAGGAGCGAGCCUCUCUGGUCCCGACGCGGGUGGCCCGGGUCUCCUCGACUCCUGAGGAAAGCCCACCGGGCGGGGCGGGAGGUGAAGAGGCUGGGGAAGUCAGAGGUUAACCUGGGCGUCAGGGGACGUUGGAGUUGAUCCGUCAGGGUCCCGGGGCGGUCUGGGGGCAGUAGAGACGGGGCUUGGGCGCGGGGCCUGAGAGGUCAGGGGUCAGCAGGAGUGAGGCUGGGGCGUCCAGGUCCGAGAGGUCAGGGGUCAGCUGGAGAGGGGCUGGGGCGCCGGUUUCCCGGAGGUCAGGGGUCAGAAGGAACAGGGCUGCAGCGUCAGGGUCCGAGAGGUUAGGGGUCGGCAGAGGCGGAGCUGGGGCACUGGGGGUCAGGGGUCGGGGAUCAGGGCGGGGUCGGGUGCACUGGUAGCCUGCGCAUGGGCCUCCAGCUUCGCGCGCUGUUGGGAGCCUUCGGACGGUGGACCCUGCGCCUGGGACCGCGUCCGUCCUGCUCGCCGCGCAUGGCCGGGAACGCGGAGCCGCCGCCCGCCGGAGCCGCAUGCCCCCAGGACCGGAGGUCCUGCAGCGGCCGGGCCGGGGGCGACCGCGUCUGGGAGGACGGAGAACAUCCGGCGAAGAAGCUCAAGAGCGGUGGCGACGAGGAGCGGCGCGAGAAGCCGCCCAAGCGGAAGAUCGUGCUGCUCAUGGCCUAUUCGGGCAAGGGCUACCACGGCAUGCAGAGGAAUGUCGGGUCCUCACAAUUCAAAACAAUUGAAGAUGACUUGGUGUCCGCCCUCGUCCGGUCAGGCUGUAUUCCUGAAAAUCAUGGUGAGGACAUGAGGAAAAUGUCCUUCCAGCGCUGCGCCCGGACAGACAAGGGUGUGUCCGCAGCCGGCCAGGUGGUAUCCCUGAAGGUGUGGCUGAUUGACGACAUUCUAGAAAAGAUCAACAGCCACCUUCCCUCUCACAUUCGGAUUCUGGGACUGAAGCGGGUCACGGGCGGGUUUAACUCCAAGAACAGAUGUGAUGCCAGGACCUAUUGCUACCUGCUGCCCACGUUUGCCUUUGCGCACAAGGACCGGGACGUUCAGGAUGAGACCUACCGCCUGAGCGCCGAGACGCUGCAGCAGGUCAACAGGCUCCUGGCCUGCUACAAGGGCACGCACAACUUCCACAAUUUCACCUCGCAGAAGGGGCCGCAGGAUCCCAGUGCCUGCCGCUACAUCCUGGAGAUGUACUGCGAGGAACCCUUUGUGCGGGAGGGCCUGGAGUUUGCGGUGAUCAGGGUGAAGGGCCAGAGCUUCAUGAUGCAUCAGAUCCGGAAGAUGGUCGGCCUGGUGGUGGCCAUUGUGAAGGGUUAUGCCCCUGAGAGCGUGCUGGAGCGCAGCUGGGGCACAGAGAAGGUGGACGUGCCCAAGGCGCCCGGACUCGGCCUGGUCCUGGAGAGGGUGCACUUCGAGAAGUACAACCAGCGCUUUGGCAACGAUGGGCUGCAUGAGCCGCUGGACUGGGCGCAGGAGGAAGGAAAGGUCGCAGCCUUCAAGGAGGAGCACAUCUACCCCACCAUCAUCGGCACCGAGCGGGACGAACGCUCCAUGGCCCAGUGGCUGAGCACCUUGCCCAUCCACAACUUCAGUGCCACCGCUCUCACGGCAGGUGGCACGGGCGCCAAGGUGCCCAGUCCCCUGGAAGGCAGUGAAGGGGACGGAGACACUGACUGAGGCGAUGGGAGCUGCCCACCAGAGUGCCUCUGAGCAGCUCACAGUGUGUGCCCAGAUGUGCCACCCCUGUGGGCAGCAAGAAGCUGGGAUCGCUGCAGCCAUGUUUUCCCGGCCAUGCCGGCGUUGUAACCUCAGGACCUUCCCUUGUAGGAACAGCCUUUCUCGAAUCUGUUUUCAGCUCUUGCAUUGCAUAGAUGAACCUCAGCAUGUAAAGAACUAUUUUUUUAAAGAAGUGAUUUUCUUAUUAAACAAGUACAAAUUUUGCUUAGUCAAUCCUUGGUUUGCCUUUUUCUUAGUCUUUUUUAACAUUUUUUUCGUCCACAGAGAUGAGCACAGCAUGGUGUCCCGUUGAGAACAGAUACGGCUGAACAAAAGAGAAAGGCCCAGGAGGUUGGCUCAGCCUGUAAUCCCAGCACUUGGGAGGCUGAGGUGGGCAGAUCGCUUGAGUACAGGAGUUCCAGACCAGCCUGGGUAAAAUGGUGAAACCGCGUCUCUGCAAAAGAUUAGCUGGGCAUGGCGGCAUGCCCUGUAGUUCAGCUGCUCAGGAGGCUGAGGUGGGAGGAUUGCCUGAGUCUGGAGAAGUCGAGGCUGCCCUGAUUGCCACUGCACUCAAAAAAAAAAAAAACAACAACAACCAAAAAAACUGGCCAGGCGUGGUGGCUCAUGCCUGUAAUCCCAACACUUCGGGAGGCUGAGGCAGGUGGAUUACUUGAGGUCGGGAGUUUGAGACCAGCCUGACCAGCAUGGAGAAACCCCGUCUCUACUAAAAAUACAAAAAUUAGCUGGGCGCGAUGGUGGGCGCCUGUAAUCCCAGCUACUUGGGAGGCUGAGGCAGGAGAAUCGCUUGAACCUGGGAGGUGGAGAUUGCAGUGAGCCAAGAUUGCGCCACUGCACUCCAGCCUGGGUGAGAGAGCCAAACUCCGUCAAAAAAAAAACAACAAAAAAACCCAGCAUCCUGCACUCUGCAGGGUGGUCCCGAGGCAGGGCUGUGGAGGGCACUGAAGCAGGGGCCCCGCUGACCUGCCGCAUCCCCGAGAGGGGUGGCAGCCACGGGCUCCUCUUCCUAGACAGCCCCAUGCGUGCAGCCUUUGCCCUGGUUGCAGGUCGGUACUCGCCUCAGCACUGUCCCGGUGCCAGGCAGGUGGGGGUUGGGGCAGAGGGCAGAAGGAAAGGGUGCAUCGCGGAACAGGCCCUUAGUGGAGCUUACUGGAAGACCCCACCAGCCGCUGCUGCACGUCAUUGGUCACAGGUGCAUCCAGCGGCCCUUCGUAGCUGCAAGGGAGGCUGGGGAAGACUGCUUUUGAAGUGGCGCUUAGCGUGGAACAAAACACACUGCGUUAGCCAGGAGCAGGGGAUCCUUGGCUGGCGGGCUGCCAGGAGCCCAGGGAGGGGCUCAGCGGAGGAAGUGCCGUGCAUACACGUGGCCUCCCAGCCUGCAGCCCGUGGGCGCACGUGACCAAUGCACGAGUGCCUGAUGCCCCAGCGGUGCACACAACUAAUGCGCAUGCGCCUGACGUGCCAACAAUGCAUGUGACUAAUGCGCAGUCGCCUGUCGCCCCAGCAGUGCGUGAGUGACAUGUGCACGUGCCCAUGAUGCGGUGGACACCGUGUGUGAGAAGUGGGGCAGGACAGGUGGGAUUGGGAGAUGCUUCAGGCAGUGAGCUCCUAGGGCGUGGGGUGCCCAAGAGAGUGGAGCUGGUUUUAGGGAUUUUGGCCAGAGGAGCAGUGGGGCUCACUGCUUCGGGAGCCAGGGAGUGCAGGUGUGAGGCCCACUGGGCUUUGGGUUUGAGGGAUGGAUGAGCUGGGCCGUUAACUGGAACGGGAGACAGGGAAAGGAAUGGGUUUGGAGAACAAGCAGGAGCUUGGUUCUAAGCAUGUUAAUUUUACCUGGGAUAGACAGGACUUUAUUUUUUAUUUUUAUUUUGUUUGAGACGGAGUCUCGCUGUGUUGCCCAGCCUGGAGUGCAGUGGCGCGAUCUCGGCUCACUGCAACCUGCGCCUCCCGGGCUCAAGCGAUUCUCCUUCCUCAGCCUCCAGAGUAGCUGAGAGUACAGGUGCCCGCUGCCACGCCCGGCUGAUUUUUGUAUUUUUGGUAGAGACAGGGUUUCACCAUGUUGGUCAGGCUGGUCUCAAACUCCUAAGCUCAGGUGAUCCACCCGCCUUGGCCUCCCAAAGUGCUGGGAUUACAGGCGUGAGCCACCGUGCCCGGCCUGGGUGACCCAUUUAAAUCACUUUUGAUGAUCCUGGGGUAUGUGACAUUUUAAAAUAAUAUGUAUAUAUGGAAGGAAAUAAAAAACUAUAAAAAAGGGAA